AUGCUGCUGCCCUGCCACUGGGUGUUGGAUGCCACCUUCAGUGAUGGCAGUCUAGGCCAGUGGGUGAAAAACACAUGUGCCACAUAUGCCUUAUCCCCAGUGGUGCUCCCACCUCAGCCCCAGCCCCGGAAAAAGGCCACAGAUAAGGACUAUUCUGCCUUUCAUCUUGGGCAUCUGAGGGAGGUGAGGCUUUUUCUGAGGGGUGGAACUUCAGAUCAGCGAAUGGAUAGUCUUGUCCUCUGCCCCACAUACUUCAAGCUCUGGAGGACCCUAUCAGGGUCCCCAGGUUUACAACUUUCUGACUUGCAUUUUGGGAGUCAGCCGGAGGGGAAGUUUUCUCUGAGGAGGGCAGUUUCAGUUAAGCAGAGGGAGGAACCCCAGGACUGGCCACUCAACGAGAAGAGAACUCUGUGGAAGGACAGUGACCUUCCAACAUGGAGGAGAGGCACAGGCUACACCCUUUCCCUUCCUGCCGUCAGCCCUGGAAAAAGGUUGUGGGGGGAGAAAGCGGGGAGCUUGCCAGAGAGCGAGCCCUUGUUCACUUAUACACUGGAUGAAAAGGUGGACAAGUUGGUGCAGUUUCUUCUCCUCAAAUAUCAAGCAAAAGAGCCUCUCACAAGAGCAGAGAUGCAGAUGAAUGUCAUCAACACAUACACGGGCUACUUUCCUAUGAUCUUCAGGAAAGCCCGUGAGUUCAUAGAGAUUCUUUUUGGCAUUUCCCUGACAGAAGUGGACCCCGACCAUUUCUAUGUCUUUGUAAACACAUUAGACCUCACCUGUGAGGGGAGUCUGAGUGAUGAGCAGGGCAUGCCCCAGAACCGCCUCCUGAUUCUUAUUCUGAGUGUGAUCUUCAUAAAGGGCAACUGUGCAUCUGAGGAGGUCAUCUGGGAAGUGCUGAAUGCAAUAGGGCCCUGGUCAGCCUUGGCAGGGUUCGCGGAUGUGCUUUCCCGACUUGCACUGUGGGAGUCUGAAGGACCUGAAGCAUUUUGCGAGGAGUCUGGACUCAGGUCAGCAGAGGGAAGCGUCUUAGACCUGGCCAAUCCUCAAGGACUUGCAGGCCACAGACAGGAAGAUGGCCGCCGAGGGCUGACCGAGGCGUCCCCACAACAGAAGAAGGGAGGAGAAGAUGAGGAUAUGCCUGCUGCUGGGAUGCCACCUCUUCCCCAGAGUCCUCCUGAGAUUCCUCCCCAGGGUCCUCCCAAGAUCUCUCCCCAGGGUCCUCCGCAGAGUCCUCCCCAGAGUCCUCUAGACUCCUGCUCAUCCCCUCUUUUGUGGACCCGAUUGGAUGAGGAGUCCAGCAGUGAAGAGGAGGAUACAGCUACUUGGCAUGCCUUGCCAGAAAGUGAAUCCUUGCCCAGGUAUGCCCUGGAUGAAAAGGUGGCUGAGUUGGUGCAGUUUCUUCUCCUCAAAUAUCAAACAAAAGAGCCUGUCACAAAGGCAGAGAUGCUGACGACUGUCAUCAAGAAGUAUAAGGACUAUUUUCCCAUGAUCUUCGGGAAAGCCCAUGAGUUCAUAGAGCUAAUUUUUGGCAUUGCCCUGACUGAUAUGGACCCCGACAACCACUCCUAUUUCUUUGAAGACACAUUAGACCUCACCUAUGAGGGAAGCCUGAUUGAUGACCAGGGCAUGCCCAAGAACUGUCUCCUGAUUCUUAUUCUCAGUAUGAUCUUCAUAAAGGGCAGCUGUGUCCCCGAGGAGGUCAUCUGGGAAGUGUUGAGUGCAAUAGGGCCCAUUCAGAGGCCAGCAAGAGAAGUCUUAGAGUUUUUAUCCAAGCUAUCCAGUAUCAUCCCUAGUGCCUUUCCAUCCUGGUACAUGGAUGCUUUGAAAGAUAUGGAAGACAGAGCCCAGGCCAUAAUUGACACCACAGAUGAUGCUACUGCCAUGGCCAGUGCAAGCCCCAGUGUCAUGUCCACCAACUUCUGUCCUGAGUGA